GCAGAGCUGGAGAGCCGCGGCUGGGACCGGAGUGGGGAGCGCGGCGUGGAGGUGCCACCCGGCGCGGGUGGCGGAGAGAUCAGAAGCCUCUUCCCCAAGCCGAGCCAACCUCAGCGGGGACCCGGGCUCAGGGACGCGGCGGCGGCGGCGGCGACUGCAGUGGCUGGACGAUGGCAGCGUCCGCCGGAGCCGGGGCGGUGAUUGCAGCCCCAGACAGCCGGCGCUGGCUGUGGUCGGUGCUGGCGGCGGCGCUUGGGCUCUGAAUACCGUGACCAGCUGAUCAAUGCCAUAGAUCUGUGAGAGUCAGACUUCCAGCUGUGCCUUGACUCUGCUGUCCAUCAUGUGACAGCUGGAGUAUCAGCCUUGGAAGUAUAUACGCCAAAAGAAAUCUUCGUGGCAAAUGGUACACAAGGGAAGCUGACCUGCAAGUUCAAGUCUACUAGUACGACUGGCGGGUUGACCUCAGUCUCCUGGAGCUUCCAGCCAGAGGGGGCCGACACUACUGUGUCGUUUUUCCACUACUCCCAAGGGCAAGUGUACCUUGGGAAUUAUCCACCAUUUAAAGACAGAAUCAGCUGGGCUGGAGACCUUGACAAGAAAGAUGCAUCAAUCAACAUAGAAAAUAUGCAGUUUAUACACAAUGGCACCUAUAUCUGUGAUGUCAAAAACCCUCCUGACAUCGUUGUCCAGCCUGGACACAUUAGGCUCUAUGUCGUAGAAAAAGAGAAUUUGCCUGUGUUUCCAGUUUGGGUAGUGGUGGGCAUAGUUACUGCUGUGGUCCUAGGUCUCACUCUGCUCAUCAGCAUGAUUCUGGCUGUCCUCUAUAGAAGGAAAAACUCUAAACGGGAUUACACUGGCUGCAGUACAUCAGAGAGUUUGUCACCAGUUAAGCAGGCUCCUCGGAAGUCCCCCUCCGACACUGAGGGUCUUGUAAAGAGUCUGCCUUCUGGAUCUCACCAGGGCCCAGUCAUAUAUGCACAGUUAGACCACUCCGGCGGACAUCACAGUGACAAGAUUAACAAGUCAGAGUCUGUGGUGUAUGCGGAUAUCCGAAAGAAUUAAGAGAAUACCUAGAACAUAUCCUCAGCAAGAAACAAAACCAAACUGGACUCUCGUGCAGAAAAUGUAGCCCAUUACCACAUGUAGCCUUGGAGACCCAGGCAAGGACAAGUACACGUGUACUCACAGAGGGAGAGAAAGAUGUGUACAAAGGAUAUGUAUAAAUAUUCUAUUUAGUCAUCCUGAUAUGAGGAGCCAGUGUUGCAUGAUGAAAAGAUGGUAUGAUUCUACAUAUGUACCCAUUGUCUUGCUGUUUUUGUACUUUCUUUUCAGGUCAUUUACAAUUGGGAGAUUUCAGAAACAUUCCUUUCACCAUCAUUUAGAAAUGGUUUGCCUUAAUGGAGACAAUAGCAGAUCCUGUAGUAUUUCCAGUAGACAUGGCCUUUUAAUCUAAGGGCUUAAGACUGAUUAGUCUUAGCAUUUACUGUAGUUGGAGGAUGGAGAUGCUAUGAUGGAAGCAUACCCAGGGUGGCCUUUAGCACAGUAUCAGUACCAUUUAUUUGUCUGCCGCUUUUAAAAAAUACCCAUUGGCUAUGCCACUUGAAAACAAUUUGAGAAGUUUUUUUGAAGUUUUUCUCACUAAAAUAUGGGGCAAUUGUUAGCCUUACAUGUUGUGUAGACUUACUUUAAGUUUGCACCCUUGAAAUGUGUCAUAUCAAUUUCUGGAUUCAUAAUAGCAAGAUUAGCAAAGGAUAAAUGCCGAAGGUCACUUCAUUCUGGACACAGUUGGAUCAAUACUGAUUAAGUAGAAAAUCCAAGCUUUGCUUGAGAACUUUUGUAACGUGGAGAGUAAAAAGUAUCGGUUUUAUUCUUUGCUGAUGUCCUUUCUGCUUGAAAUAACAGUCACCAUACAGCUAAAGGAGAGGAGUUUCUUUCCUUCUAAGUAGGCAGAAAUGGUAUCAUUAUGUUGCCGCUCUCCAAUCUCCCAGAGCUCGCUCUCUAGAGAAUCACCUUCUUUCGCUUUUUUUUUUUUUUUUGAGGUAGAGUCUCACUAUGUUGCCCAGACUAGCCUUGAACUCUUGGGCUCAAGUGAUUCUCCCUCCUCAGCCUCCCGAGUAGCUGGAACGAACUAUAGUUGCACCACUGCAGCUGGCAAGAAUCACCUUCUUUAUAAAGCGUCAGUCAUGCUUCCAGCAAGAGGCAGCAUCAGUCAUGGCUUUAUAACAGCUUCAUGGUGCCUCAAAGACUGUUGAGGUUAAUGAGAGCCUAGAUUAGACAGUUUGGCUGUCCUUCCCUAAAACUUGUUUUCUCCUAUUCACUACUCCCCACCGCACUUAAAAUCUAUGAGUUUUUACUUUUUACUGGGAAUGGAAAGUGUGGUGAAGAUCAUUCAACACUUAUGUUGUCAUUUCUCCCAUUUUCUGAAUUUUUUUUUAAAUUUCCCCCCUUUUAAAAUUGUUCGAAAGCCCACAGUUAUGGAAAGAAUUACUGUCUAGAUGGUCUGCAGAACGUGUUUGGGGUGAGUGGGAGUGAGGGGCAAUGUUACUUUUUCUCCCUGUAGUUUGGAGUCCAUUAUGAGCUGCUGCUUUUUCUUCUCAUCUUGUCAUCUUCUGGGGAUGUUUGAAGGCUGAGUUCCAACAGAAUUCACAAAGGGAAUAAAACAGGAUUGAGAUUUUGAGGUGUGCACAAGGUGGUAAGAUAAAGGGCAUAUGAGCUUCAAAACUAAUGCUGUUGCAUACAUGAAGCCUUUUGUUUUUUGAGGAGCUAUUUUUGUUAUUCUUGUAACGCUCCACCUUACAUGCCACAUCUGUGUGAGUCAACAGGGAUCAGGUUUGGUCACCACACAUGUCUGAAGCUGGGCAGCGUCUGCUCUGUGUUCUGUGUGGAAUGGAGAAAAAAACGCCUGCCCUGCUGCCUUCCAUGUUCAUAGGCCCAGCCCAAGAGAGUGACACACAGUGCUGGCCCUGAGACAUUUCCACAAAGUGGUCAACUCUGCCUUGCAUCCUAAAACUUUUUGGGCAUCUAUUUUGAAAACUAUAGGAGCCUUUGGAAGGCCUCUUAUGUUUGGAGGGGAAGGGUGUUGAGAUUGUCACCAUCCUUCAAGCUGAGACUCCUGGUGAGCCUUUGCCACCAUGAAAACCACAUAGCUGACCAGGGCUGUGCUUGAGGUACAGAGGACACACAUUGUAGACAGGCCUGUGUCAUGUUUCCUUACAGUCGUUUUUUACAGAGAAAAGGGGCAUUGUUUUUUCACUGCUUUCUCAACAGUUCCUGUGAAUAAAUGAAACAUUUCGGAGCUCCCUGAGAGCAAGAGCCUUCACUUCUUCUUGCGGUGCCGGGACCAUGUGUUGGUGAAGCUGGUGCUGUGGGGGCCACUCACUCGAAUGACACCUGGAGGCCUGUUCCUCCCUUACCACUCCCUUCCCCAGCCCGACUUCUUGGCCUCCUGCCCAACCAGACACCUCAAACUCUGUCAGUGCCCUGGCAUUCUGGCAGAGAAUCCUCACCAGUUCUCACCAACCUUCCCCCCAGGCAAGGGCAGCUGCCAGCAUGGUGCUCUGCCAGGACAGGUUUCCCUGAAGGAAGCUGCUCACACUGAGAUGAGCCUCUCAGGGCAGGACCUCUUCCCAAGCCCUGCACACCCACCCCUGCAGCCCUUUUGGCUCCCCUUUUCCCUGUGCCUCAGCACUCCUUUCCUGGUUGCAGAUAACGAACUAAGGUUGCCUAAAGGGCAGAUCUGCCCUCUCCAUGUCUUCGUCCUGGCAAACAGGGUCGUCUUAAAAUUAUGCGCUAAUUCUGUAUGGGAGCACUCAAAAGGCAUUACUUAGAGAUUGAAAUUUCAAACUAUCUCUAGUUUUUCAAUGGAAAUAUAUCAGCUAGGGAAAAACCAUCAAGCUCAUUAUUAUUUUUUGAUCUUCAGUUGUAUUUUUGUGAAUAUUUUAAUACAUCUUUUUCAAUUUCUGAAUUGUGUUGUGUGCUCAUUUUGACCAGAAUAGAAAAAGAGAUAUGCCUUUCACUCAUAUCAUUCCAGCUACACCUGCCUUCUUUUCUUCAAAAAUGCCGUCCGUGUGCCUGCUUCUGGGCCUUUGCACAUGCUGUUCCCUGGGCCUGAAGCAUGCCUUCUGCCAAUAUUCCUGUGGUUUGCUCUCUGACUUCCUUUAAGCCUCUGCUCAAAUGUUACCUCCUCAGGGAGACCUUCUGUGAUAUAUAAAAGAGCAAGCCCCCCACCCCACCGCCUCAGCCUUCCUGGCCCCCUCAGUUCUGCUCUAGUUACUCUAUUUCUCUCCCUCUUUCCCAGUACACACUUGUCUGUUCUCCCGCAUUAGAACAUAGUUAACAAGAGACCAGAACCUUGCUGUUUUGUUCACUGCUCCGUCUGCAGUAAAGGGAACAGCACCUGGCACUUAGCUGCUCAAUACAUGUUACGUGGAUGGAUGAGUAGGUGGAAGCAUUCAUCCAUUCAGCAACCUACACUGAGAACAAUCCUGUGCCAAGCACUGUGCUAAGCAUAAGGAAACAAAACAAGACAAAGCUCCUCAAGGAGCUUGCCACAGGGUGGAGGUGACAGGUGACAUGAAUGGAAGUAACUAGUAGUUACCAAAUACUUGGUGUGAGCCAGGCACUUUGCAUUUCUUUCUCUAUUAUUUCUGUGAGUUAACAGUAAUUGUACUAAUCUUAAUCCCAUUGUUUGAAAGAUUAUAUGGCUUACCCAGGGCCACUUAGCUAAUAAAGGAACAGAGAAGAGGGGCUGGGCCUGGGGCCGCUGUUUGAUCCACAGCCUUGUUCCUAACCACUAUGCCCUGUGGCCUCUCACACCAAAAGGAAGUACCAAACUGCUUCCUUACUCAAAUAAAUGUGCUGAAAUGCAGUUGCAGUUUUCUCCCAGUCCCUUAGGAGCUGGUUAGAGAGUCCCUUAGGAACUUGAGAGGGUAGUGUAGUCUAGGUGGUAGGCACAGAUGUCUGAGAGCUUUAACCUCAGUCUGGAAGACAAUGUGGUGACUUAAUUUGUUGAGAACUAUGUUACAAAUAAUGUGUUACUAAUAAAACAUUGAGGCUUCGCA